ACACAUGUUCUCAGGACCUCCUGAGUGCUGAUCACUCAUAUUUGGCUCAGAAAAAUCUCUUCUAAUAUAUUACAGAGUUUGACUCUUUUUGUCCACAAUAAUUUGGUGCCUGAACACGUGAGGCCUCAGAUAAGACUCAGGACCCCAAAGGAGUUGUCUCAACCUGGAGCUAAGGUACCAGCAGGGGCCCACUGAAAGCCUCCAGGAUUUUGAGCUUCUUCUCUGCCAGAAGUGGAAGUUGUUGUUUAAGGAUCCUACUUCUAGUUGGGAGAUACAUUCUAAAGGGUCUUCUCCAUUGCUUUUCUCCCCAAAUUAAUCUCGAUUUGGCUUGUCUGUUCACAUUUGCAUGAGGAACUGAACUGUUGUUUUCAUAGGGAAACGAGAGACUGUGUUUCCUCAGCUUAAAAAAGAAAGGGCAUUUUGCUCCUCCCAGCCAAAAUGUGGGAAGUGAUGAGGGGUGCUUGUGGGAAUGUCUGGGGGUGGAUGGACCCCAUCGUGAUGUGAGUGGCCUACAGGGAACACCCAACAAAAUGAGUUUUAAAAAGGCUUGUCCAGGAAGCACAUAUGGGAGCUGGUCACUCUGCAUUUUGGGCCCUCCUGGAGGUGUUUAGACCUUCCGAGAGAGAAACUGAGACACAUGAGAGGGAAGAAAUGACUCAGUGGUGAGACCCUGUGGAGUCCCACCCACAACCAGCACACUGUGACCCACUGCACAAACCUCUAGCCCACAGCUCACUUCCUCCUUUAAGAAGAGAAGAGAAAAGAGGAGAGGAGAGGAGGAACAGAAAAGAAAAGAAAAGAAAAAGUGGGAAACAAAUAAUCUAAGAAUGAGGAGAAAGCAAGAAGAGUGACCCCCUUGUGGGCACUCCAUUGGUUUUAUGGCGCCUCUACUUUCUGGAGUUUGUGUAAAACAAAAAUAUUAUGGUCUUUGUGCACAUUUACAUCAAGCUCAGCCUGGGCGGCACAGCCAGAUGCGAGAUGCGUCUCUGCUGAUCUGAGUCUGCCUGCAGCAUGGACCUGGGUCUUCCCUGAAGCAUCUCCAGGGCUGGAGGGACGACUGCCAUGAUGACAGCACCCCAUGAGAAGAAGGACCCAGCCUCCGAUUGGCCACACUCUGUGUGUCUCUCUAUCCUGCCAGCACCGAGGGCUCAUCCAUCCACAGAGCAGGGCAGUGGGAGGAGACGCCAUGACCCCCAUCCUCACGGUCCUGAUCUGUCUCGGGCUGAGUCUGGGCCCCCGGACCCACGUGCAGGCAGGGCACCUCCCCAAGCCCACCCUCUGGGCUGAACCAGGCUCUGUGAUCACCCAGGGGAGUCCUGUGACCCUCAGGUGUCAGGGGGGCCAGGAGACCCAGGAGUACCGUCUAUAUAGAGAAAAGAAAACAGCACCCUGGAUUACACGGAUCCCACAGGAGCUUGUGAAGAAGGGCCAGUUCCCCAUCCCAUCCAUCACCUGGGAACACACAGGGCGGUAUCGCUGUUACUAUGGUAGCGACACUGCAGGCCGCUCAGAGAGCAGUGACCCCCUGGAGCUGGUGGUGACAGGAGCCUACAUCAAACCCACCCUCUCAGCCCAGCCCAGCCCCGUGGUGAACUCAGGAGGGAAUGUAACCCUCCAGUGUGACUCACAGGUGGCAUUUGAUGGCUUCAUUCUGUGUAAGGAAGGAGAAGAUGAACACCCACAAUGCCUGAACUCCCAGCCCCAUGCCCGUGGGUCGUCCCGCGCCAUCUUCUCCGUGGGCCCCGUGAGCCCGAGUCGCAGGUGGUGGUACAGGUGCUAUGCUUAUGACUCGAACUCUCCCUAUGAGUGGUCUCUACCCAGUGAUCUCCUGGAGCUCCUGGUCCUAGGUGUUUCUAAGAAGCCAUCACUCUCAGUGCAGCCAGGUCCUAUCGUGGCCCCUGAGGAGACCCUGACUCUGCAGUGUGGCUCUGAUGCUGGCUACAACAGAUUUGUUCUGUAUAAGGACGGGGAACGUGACUUCCUUCAGCUCGCUGGCGCACAGCCCCAGGCUGGGCUCUCCCAGGCCAACUUCACCCUGGGCCCUGUGAGCCGCUCCUACGGGGGCCAGUACAGAUGCUACGGUGCACACAACCUCUCCUCCGAGUGGUCGGCCCCCAGCGACCCCCUGGACAUCCUGAUCGCAGGACAGUUCUAUGACAGAGUCUCCCUCUCGGUGCAGCCGGGCCCCACGGUGGCCUCAGGAGAGAACGUGACCCUGCUGUGUCAGUCACAGGGAUGGAUGCAAACUUUCCUUCUGACCAAGGAGGGGGCAGCUGAUGACCCAUGGCGUCUAAGAUCAACGUACCAAUCUCAAAAAUACCAGGCUGAAUUCCCCAUGGGUCCUGUGACCUCAGCCCAUGCGGGGACCUACAGGUGCUACGGCUCACAGAGCUCCAAACCCUACCUGCUGACUCACCCCAGUGACCCCCUGGAGCUCGUGGUCUCAGGACCGUCUGGGGGCCCCAGCUCCCCGACAACAGGCCCCACCUCCACAUCUGCAGGCCCUGAGGACCAGCCCCUCACCCCCACCGGGUCGGAUCCCCAGAGUGGUCUGGGAAGGCACCUGGGGGUUGUGAUCGGCAUCUUGGUGGCCGUCAUCCUACUGCUCCUCCUCCUCCUCCUCCUCUUCCUCAUCCUCCGACAUCGACGUCAGGGCAAACACUGGACAUCGACCCAGAGAAAGGCUGAUUUCCAACAUCCUGCAGGGGCUGUGGGGCCAGAGCCCACAGACAGAGGCCUGCAGUGGAGGUCCAGCCCAGCUGCCGAUGCCCAGGAAGAAAACCUCUAUGCUGCCGUGAAGCACACACAGCCUGAGGAUGGGGUGGAGAUGGACACUCGGCAGAGCCCACACGAUGAAGACCCCCAGGCAGUGACGUAUGCCGAGGUGAAACACUCCAGACCUAGGAGAGAAAUGGCCUCUCCUCCUUCCCCACUGUCUGGGGAAUUCCUGGACACAAAGGACAGACAGGCGGAAGAGGACAGGCAGAUGGACACUGAGGCUGCUGCAUCUGAAGCCCCCCAGGAUGUGACCUACGCCCAGCUGCACAGCUUGACCCUCAGACGGGAGGCAACUGAGCCUCCUCCAUCCCAGGAAGGGCCCUCUCCAGCUGUGCCCAGCAUCUACGCCACUCUGGCCAUCCACUAGCCCAGGGGGGGACGCAGACCCCACACUCCAUGGAGUCUGGAAUGCAUGGGAGCUGCCCCCCCAGUGGACACCAUUGGACCCCACCCAGCCUGGAUCUACCCCAGGAGACUCUGGGAACUUUUAGGGGUCACUCAAUUCUGCAGUAUAAAUAACUAAUGUCUCUACAAUUUUGAAAUAAAGCAACAGACUUCUCAAUAAUCAAUGAAGUAGCUGAGAAAACUAAGUCAGAAAGUGCAUUAAACUGAAUCACAAUGUAAAUAUUACACAUCAAGCGAUGAAACUGGAAAACUACAAGCCACGAAUGAAUGAAUUAGGAAAGAAAAAAAGUAGGAAAUGAAUGAUCUUGGCUUUCCUAUAAGAAAUUUAGGGCAGGGCACGGUGGCUCACGCCUGUAAUUCCAGCACUUUGGGAGGCCGAGGCGGGCAGAUCACGAGUUCAGGAGAUCGAGACCAUCUUGGCCAACAUGGUGAAACCCUGUCUCUCCUAAAAAUACAAAAAUUAGCUGGAUGUGGUGGCAGUGCCUGUAAUCCCAGCUAUUUGGGAGGCUGAGGCAGGAGAAUCGCUUGAACCAGGGAGUCAGAGGUUUCAGUGAGCCAAGAUCGCACCACUGCUCUCCAGCCUGGCGACAGAGGGAGACUCCAUCUCAAAUUAAAAAAAAAAAAAAAAAAGAAAGAAAAAGAGAAAAAAGAAAUUUAGAAGAAUAACAAGUUAUUCCAAAUGAAGGCGUAAGAAAGGGAAUAAUAACAAUAAUAAGAGGAGUUGUUCAUGAGGAAAAACCAAAGCUUGAAAAUUCAACAAAGCCAGUGAAGCUCAUUCUUGAAAACAUGAAUCACACUCAUGAAUUCUAACUACAAUGAAAAAGAGAAAGAAAGAGCAGGCAUGCAUUUCCAUAUGGGAGUGAGCCAGCAGACAGCCCUACAGAUCGUACACACGUUUUCCAAAACUAACAAUGGAACAGGCGGCAAACCUAUGCCAAUAUACUAGAAAUUGCAGAUUAAAUAGAUGAAAUAUUCUAAACUGGAGUUUACAUAAUGAACAUAAGAGUAAUCAGAGAAUCUGACUCAUUUUAGAUGUGUGUGUGUGUGUAUAUAUAUGUGUGUGUGUGUGAAAAACAUUGACUAUAAUAAAAAUAAUCUCGAGUUCA